AGCUUGCGGCCUGUGUCUAUGGUCGGGCCCUCUGCGUCCAGCUGCUCCGGACCGAGCUCGGGUGUAUGGGGCCGUAGGAACCGGCUCCGGGGCCCCGAUAACGGGCCGCCCCCACAGCACCCCGGGCUGGCGUGAGGGUCUCCCUUGAUCUGAGAAUGGCUACCUCUCGAUAUGAGCCAGUGGCUGAAAUUGGUGUCGGUGCCUAUGGGACAGUGUACAAGGCCCGUGAUCCCCACAGUGGCCACUUUGUGGCCCUCAAGAGUGUGAGAGUCCCCAAUGGAGGAGGAGGUGGAGGAGGCCUUCCCAUCAGCACAGUUCGUGAGGUGGCUUUACUGAGGCGACUGGAGGCUUUUGAGCAUCCCAAUGUUGUCCGGCUGAUGGACGUCUGUGCCACAUCCCGAACUGACCGGGAGAUCAAGGUAACCCUGGUGUUUGAGCAUGUAGACCAGGACCUAAGGACAUAUCUGGACAAGGCACCCCCACCAGGCUUGCCAGCCGAAACGAUCAAGGAUCUGAUGCGCCAGUUUCUAAGAGGCCUAGAUUUCCUUCAUGCCAAUUGCAUCGUUCACCGAGAUCUGAAGCCAGAGAACAUUCUGGUGACAAGUGGUGGAACAGUCAAGCUGGCUGACUUUGGCCUGGCCAGAAUCUACAGCUACCAGAUGGCACUUACACCCGUGGUUGUUACACUCUGGUACCGAGCUCCCGAAGUUCUUCUGCAGUCCACAUAUGCAACACCUGUGGACAUGUGGAGUGUUGGCUGUAUCUUUGCAGAGAUGUUUCGUCGAAAGCCUCUCUUCUGUGGAAACUCUGAAGCCGACCAGUUGGGCAAAAUCUUUGACCUGAUUGGGCUGCCUCCAGAGGAUGACUGGCCUCGAGAUGUAUCCCUGCCCCGUGGAGCCUUUCCCCCCAGAGGGCCCCGCCCAGUGCAGUCGGUGGUACCUGAGAUGGAGGAGUCGGGAGCACAGCUGCUGCUGGAAAUGCUGACUUUUAACCCACACAAGCGAAUCUCUGCCUUUCGAGCUCUGCAGCACUCUUAUCUACAUAAGGAUGAAGGUAAUCCGGAGUGAGCAAUGGAGUGGCUGCCAUGGAAGGAAGAAAAGCUGCCAUUUCCCUUCUGGACACUGAGAGGGCAAUCUUUGCCUUUAUCUCUGAGGCUAUGGAGGGUCCUCCUCCAUCUUUCUACAGAGAUUACUUUGCUGCCUUAAUGACAUUCCCCUCCCACCUCUCCUUUUGAGGCUUCUCCUUCUCCUUCCCAUUUCUCUACACUAAGGGGUAUGUUCCCUCUUGUCCCUUUCCCUACCUUUAUAUUUGGGGUCCUUUUUUAUACAGGAAAAACAAAACAAAGAAAUAAUGGUCUUUUUUUUUUUUUUAAUGUUUCUUCCUCUGUUUGGCUUUGCCAUUGUGCGAUUUGGAAAAACCACUUGGAAGAAGGGACUUUCCUGCAAAACCUUAAAGACUGGUUAAAUUACAGGGCCUAGGAAGUCAGUGGAGCCCCUUGACUGACAAAGCUUAGAAAGGAACUGAAAUUGCUUCUUUGAAUAUGGAUUUUAGGCGGGGCGUGGUGGCUCACGCCUAUAAUCCCAGCACGUUGGGAGGCCAACGCGGGUGGAUCACCUGAGGUCAGGAGUUCGAGACCAGCCUGACUAACAUGGUGAAACCCUGUCUCUACUAAAAAUACAAAAUUAGUCAGGCGUGGUGGUGCACACCUGUAAUCCCAGCUACUUGGGAGACUGAGGCAGGAGGAUCGCUUGAACCCGGGAGGCAGAGGUUGCGGUGAGCCGAGAUCAUGCCAUUGCACUCCAGCCUGGGCAACAGAGCAAGACUCUGUGUCAAAAAAAAAAAAAGAAUAUAGAUUUUUAAAUGGC